AUGAAGUCUGAGAUGAGAAUUCGAUAUGGAGGGCAAGUUCUUCUAGUCAAUGAAAACCAUCAGCCAAUCACCAACAAAACUGUAGAUGUUCAUGUGAAUACUAGAUACUAUUUCAGUGCAACUACUGAUGAGCAUGGUUUGGUGAACAUUUCCAUGGACACCACCAACUACAUAUCACCUUUUCUCACAGUUUCAAUCAAAGCAAGAGGAAAAAUCUCCCAAUCAGGAAUCCAUGUGUUAUCCAUUGAACAAGGAAACAUGAAAGGGGUGUUUUCCUUCUCCUUUCGAGUGGAAUCAGACUCUGCUCCUAGUGCUCAUCUGCUUGUUUACACUGUUUUACCUAAUGGAGAAAUUGUUGCAGACACUGACAAGCUUGAGAUUGAAAACUGUUUUGCCAACAAGGUAAAUUUGAGAUUCUCCUCAGCUCAGAGCCUGCCAGCCUCAAACACCCGCCUGAAGGUGAGAGCCACCCCCCUCUCCCUUUGUGCCCUCCGUGCUGUAGACCAGAGUGUGCUGCUAAUGAAGCCUGAAGCUGAGCUCUCACCUAAAUCUGUCUAUAACUUGCUACCAGUAAAGAGUCCAUUUACCUUUAGAGCUGGAGGUCCUGCGGAUGAAUAUGAUGAAGAGUGCAACAACGCAAAAGACACAACUCACAGCGGAAUCACUUCCACACCGAAGCAAGUCCUGGAGGGGGAUGACAUUUACAGUAUCUUCACGAAUAGAAGAAAAAUGGUGCUUUAUUGGGUUGGUUUAAGAUGAAAACCUGUUUUUCUAAGUAUUGGAUCUUGAGACUGCAGCAACUUCUUGGUAAGUUAGCCCCAAAUAAUACUUUUUCCUCAAAUAGAGGAUUUUUAAGCAAUUAUUAUUUUCUCUUUGACAUCAAAAUCAACUAACUUUUUGUUUUUGCUUUUAAUAGUCUUGCCAUUUUAGAUCUUCCUUGUCCAUGAUGGAGUCAAUACCUGAAUUAGUCAGAAUUAGAUUCAAUGGCAGUAACAAACAAACUCCCACAUCUCAGCGGGUAAGCACCUAACGGUUUGGUUUUUGCUCACACAAAAUCUACUUGUGAGUUCAGACACUCUCCAGAACAGCCCCGUGCCAAACAGUGAGUCAGAGAGAACCAGUCUGCUUUCCUCUGGUGACUCUGCCAUCGCCAACGUGGCUUUCAAGGUCAUACCCAUGGGGAAGGAGGUUGCACUUGACUCUUAAAGCCAGGAGUGGGAAUGGUAUACAUCACUUCCGCCCAUGUUCCUGCCCUGAAUGCAAAGGAGGCUGAGAAAUGGGAAGGCUCAUGUGGAUAUUAACUGUCUCUGUCAUAUCUUCUUAUGGAAAGAGAAGGGAUUUAUGUAAUAUUGAGCAAAAGAGAGUAAUGCAACUUUUGGCAGAUACGCUACCUCUGCAUAGUCUCUUUGUGUGUUUCAAGUAUACCUGGAAAUCAGGAAAUGUUGCAAAAGGCCUAACUCAAAAUUCUUUUCUACUGCCAUCAGGCCUAGAGAAAUUUUUCUCUGCAUGCUUGAAUGUCUACCAAAUUUACUUUUUAAUAAAAAAUGAGGAUGGCAGUAAAAAGUGUUAAAAAAAAAAAAAGAAUAAACACAUUUUAAUACAGCAGAUUCACUGCCUGGGAAGGCAAGGAGUAAUGUUCUAAUUGAAAACAAAGGAGUCAUUAAGGAUAUUUCCUCACCAGAAAAAAAAAAAAAAUCCUGUAUAGUGAAAAAAGAACACUGUUUUAAGAACAAAGGGACAAUUUUUCAUCACACUCCUAUCUGCUAUGACUAUGUGACUUUGGAAAUUUGCAGACUCACUUAACCUUUUAGAGGCUCAGUUUCUUUAAAUCUGAAGU